AGGAUCACAGGGUCACUGCUGCUUUUUGUGGGUUCUUAGAAUUAUGUGACCCUGUGAUUUUCUUUUUAUUUAUGUCUAACUCCUCAGCAAAGGAAGGCCUUACUUAACGUGAUAAACAUUCACAUUUUAUUUUAGUUAAGCAUUUCUUUAAAUGUAAGAAAUUGGAGGCUAAUAAUUAAGUGAAAUGGUGUGGGAUGUGUUGUAUAUAUGCAAAUGUGAAUUGUGAAAUAAUUAAGCUUCACAUAGGAAUAUUAUUUGAUAGCUUAUGUACUUUUUUUUUGUUUUAAUUUUUUUUUUUGAGACAGAGUCUUGCUCUGUUGCCCAGGGUGGAGUGCAGUGGUGCAAUCUCGGCUCACUGCAACCUCUGCCUCCCGUGUUCAAGCAAUUCUCCUGCCUCAGCCUCCUGAGUAGCCAGGAUCACAGGCCUGUGCCACCAUUCCCGGGUAAUUUUUGUAUUUUUAGUAGAGAUGGGUUUUCGCCAUGUUGGCCAGUCUGUUCUCAAACUCCUGACCUCAAGUGAUCUGCCUGCCUCGGCCUCCCAAAGUGCUGGGAUUACAGGUGUGAGCCACCACACCCGGCCCAACUUAUGUAUGUUUUUAAAGUGUAAAAAUAUAAACAUUAAAUGUCUAGGUAAAUUAUGUUCGGGUUUACAUUUGUAGCUUUUCAGUGAUUUUUUUUCUUAAGUUAAAAAAAAACAACCUAAUCACCAAAAUUACUAUGGUUUUAUGCUUAACAAAAACUUUCACAUGACUUACUUGGAUGAAAAUAUGAAAUUAUCUGAGGUAGGCUGUUUGUCAUUUUCCAUAUAAUACUGUAGGUAUACAGUAGAGGAAGUAAGAGUUUAUUUAUAUGGGGAAGAAGAAUUUCUUUGACAACAUCUACCAAAGUGAAAAAGAGAAAGUAGUCCUGGCUUUUAAUAGAAUUUCUAUAGUAUUUUCUUAUCAGUUUAUUACUUUUUUGAGAAAAAAAACGAAGAUUCUUUAUUUAUAUGUAAAAUUCUUAUUUGAAACAAGUGUUUUAAGAGAAUUUUCAAGGAAUUAUAUUAGUUUCAUUAUCCUUGAUAUAAAUUUAUUAAUGGUAUAUGUCAUAGGGUACACUAUUAUGAUUUUAUUUUUAAAAUAUGUAGUUAUUAAAACAAGUUGACACAACAUAUCAAAAUGGAUUAUUUAGAAACCUCCUUUAAAAUGUUGAAAAGUCUAAGACUAAGUCUAGGACUUAUGAGUAAGAAAGCUAAGUAAAAGCAGUGGUCCAAUACCCUUUUCCCAUUCCAUUUGAAAUUACCGACAGACUUUUACAGGAGAAAAUCUGUACCAAAUCUGAAAACUGGGUAAGAGGGGCAUGGAACAAAUACAGAACAUUCAAGAGAUGUGGUGGAGCUGUGAGUAAAUGCAGGAGCAGCAUCAAGCCUCCACUCCCUCUUCUAGGAAUGCAUUAUCUUCUGCUAAAGUUGAGGUGCCAUUAGCACCAGUUUGGAGGGACAAUCAGGAAGCAGUUGGAAUCCCUUUCUUUCCUACAUCAACAUAGGAUUAUGGGGGUUAAAUGGUGGUUCUCACUGGUGGAAAGCUGGUGAGUCUUCCCUGUGCUGCGGCCAGUAGUAACACCAGGAAGGAGGUGGGAUAGGCCCCAGCAAGUUCUUUAUUUAGUGUCUGGAUUGACGGAUAGAGAAAGCCGACCUCUAGUGCAGUAAAUUCACCAAACACGGGAACAAACAAGAAAUUAUAUUUUUCUUUUAGUUCCUUUGAUGCCUGCUUCUCAGACCAAUGAGUCACUGGACUAGAAAUGCAUAUUUACAUUGACUGACAAGCCUUCCUGAUUCAGAUGGGAGAGGAGGGUUCUAAUAGCAAGUGUAUAGAUACUAGGAAAAUACUCUCAUUCUGUUUUCCAUUAUUCCUUCCUCCUCCUCCUCCUUCCUCCCCCCAUGUUUCCCAGGCUGGUCUCGAACUCCUGAGUUCAAGAGAUCCCCCCCACCUCAGCCUCCCAAGUAGCUGGGACUACAUGCCCUUGCCUCUGCUUUGUUUUCCAUUAUUUUCUCACAUGUCAGGCUUCAUUAUAUGUUUCACAGUCUUUAUUAUUAUUUACCUUCCUCAGCUAGAAUGUGAGUCCACAAGGAUAGGUCUGAACUCUUUUACUCACAGCAUUUCUGACCCCCAAAUAUGUGUCUUUUGUCCUCAUACCAACCAAUUCUCCAUAUCUCCAGACACUAGCUGGGUGUUCUGCAAUUCAGUUCAAUUCUGACACUGAAGACCUGGAGUUAAUACAGACCCCACAGGUUAAGGGUUUAGUCCCACAGGACUGCUACCACUUCAGAUAACAAUUACAAGUCUGGACUACCUGUAUGUCUGACCUACUGGCAAUAAAGUUGAUGGGGGUGGGGGUUUCCACAACCUGUUCCUGAAGUUUGAUAAUUUGCUAGAAUGGCUCACAGAACUCAGGAACACUCUACUUAUGGUUAUGGGUUUAUUAUAAAGGAUACAAUUUGAGAGCUGCUAAAUGGAAGCGAUGCAUAGAGCCAGGUAUAAGAGAAGGGGUGUGGGGCUUCCAUGCCCUCUCUAGGUAUGCCACCCUCCCAGCACCAUGAUGUGUUCACCAACUCAGAAACUCUGAGUGGUGUGUUGUUUUUUUCUUUUUUUGAGAUGAAGUCUCACUCUGUCUUCAGGCUGGAGUGCAGUGGUGCGAUCUCAGCUCACUGCAGCGUCCGCUUCCUGGGUUCAAGCAAUUCUCCUGUCUCAGCCACCCAAGUAGCUGGGACUACAGGUGUGCACCACCACGCCCAGCUAAUUUUUAUGUAUUUUUUAGUAGAGACGGGGUUUCACCAUGUUGGCUAGGAUGGUCUCGAUCUCUUGACCUUGUGAUCCGCCUGCCUCAGCCUCCCAAAGUGCUAGGAUUACAGGCGUGAGCCACUGCACCCGGCCAAAACUCUGAGCUUUUAUACCAUUGUUUAGGGUUUUUAUGGAGGUUCCAUUAUGUAGGUGUGAUUGCUUAAUUAUAAGGCUAUUUUUGAUAAAAUCAGUCCCCAGCUCCUCUCUCCCCAGAGGUUGAGGAGUGGGGCUGAAGUUCCAACUGUCUGAUCAUGCCUUGAUCUUUCUAGUGACCAGCCUCUAUCCUGAAGUUAUCAAGGGGCCCACAAAGAGUCACAUCAUUAGAACAAAAGAUGCUCCUCUACCUAGGAAAUUCCAAGGGAUUUAGCAGCUGUGUGCCAGGAACCUGGGACAAAGAUCAAAUAUAUAUCACAAUAGGACUGUUGUUGUUUUCAUUUUGUCUUCAGCAUCCAUUAGAUUGUGUGGGACAUAAUAAGUGCAUUUAAUGUUUGUUGAAUAAAUGAAUCGAGCUGGCCUUGAUACUUAUUCUUCUGAAUGUUAAAUGCUGCAUCUAUGGAGAUUUGAAGGAAAGGGUUCUGACUCAAGACUUCUGGACCUUUAUUAGUUGUCACCAUAUGUGAAGGUGACAUAUUCUUAGGUAUGUUUGGGUACAGAAGUAUAUUAUCCAGGUAUUCCCUUCCUGAAGUAAUUAUGUGAAAUAUUACUCCAGCCAGUCAGAUGAUGAAUUAGAGAUGUCAAGAAUGUAGACGUUACCUAAGAGUAUUUGUAUUAAACAUUAUAAUCUGUUAACUAUAUAAUACUAAAUAGUUGUUAUAGUAUUAUUAUGAAACAUGUUAGCUAAUUAUUGGCAAAAGAUACAUAAUACAGUUAUUAUAAAGUGGGUAUUUACAUAAAUGAGCUAAAAUUUAUAUUGAUAGAUUUCCUAAUAUUAUACUGUUCUUGCAUUUCUAAAAUGAAAAUUAUACAAAUAAUCCAAAUGUAUAUUCGCCAAAUGUAAAGGUAACAUCUGGAACAGAGAUCCUUAAACAGGAGUCCAUUGACCCAUAGAAAUACAUGGGUGGCCUUUGGAGACUAUGGACACUUUGAAAAUUGAUAUAAAAUUAUAGGGGUCCAUCAUUGCUGUGUAAAAGCAAGGAAAUUUCAAAGAUGCACAAUAUCCUGAGAGCACUAAAGGCUAAGCAAGGACAAGCAGAUCAGUUUCAGUAAUAAGUCUAAAUGGAUGAAAUACUCCUGUUGAAGGAAAGAGACUCCCAGAUUGGGUUAAAAAACAAAAUCCGACUAGCUGGUACAUAUGAAGUCUCUUAAGACAGCAGGAUAGAAAGCUUGAAAGUAAACAGAUUAGCAAAUAUGUAUGUGUUAUUCCUUAGCCCAGAAGAGGUGAGAAGGAAAGUAUUAUUGUUAAACAAAACACGAAUACAGAAUAAAAAAUGAUUAAAACAAGGCAGUGAAGAUUAUUUUAUGCAAGCUAGAUAACACAUGUGCCAAAUACUAAAAGUCGACAAAACUAUAAUCAUUUGAAUAACAGAAAGACAUUGGUAGAAACAGUGUUGGUGGUUGAUUUUAAUAUACCUCUACAUUCUUGGCAAAGUAAAUAGGGGUGGUUAAAUCAGUCUAAGUAGAUGUUAAAGGCAACUCCUGCGAAUGCAUUUGAAUACAGACUUGACCCUAAAACAACUUGGGGAUUAGCAGUAUCGACUCUGUGCAGUUGAAAAUCUGCAUAGAACUUUUGACUCCUCCAAAACAUAACUACUAGUAACCUGUUGACCAGAAACCUUACUGAUAACAUAAACAGUUAAUACAUAUUUUUUAUGUUACGUGUAUUCUGUACAACAAAGUAAGCUAGACAAAAGAAAAUGUUAUUUGAAAAGUCAUAAGGAAGAGAAAACAUAUUUACUGUUCAUUAAGUGGAGGUGGUUUUCAUAAAGGUUUACAUCCUUGUUGUCUACACAUUGAAUAGACUGAGGAGGAGGAGGGGCAGGAGGGGUUUUGCUAUCUGAGGAGUGACAGAGGCAGAAGAAAAUCUGUGUAUUAACGAACCUGCACAGUUCAAACUUACAUUUUUCAAGGGUCACUGUGUGAUUGGAAUGGACAAUAUUUUAGGAAAAUAUGAAUAACUAAUAUUGACUUAAAUAGUAAAAAAUUUGAAAUUGAAUAUGCAAUCAAGCUUCUUUAGUGAAGACACCAAAUGGUGAUGACUUCAUAGAUUAGUUCUCCCAAACUUUCAAGAAAUUGUCCUACACUUUAUUUUCCAGAGCAAGAAAAAAAAAAAAAAAAAAAAAGGAAAGUUUAGAAGCUAGCAUGAUGCUGAAAACACAAUCUGUGGAUGACGUAGUAGAUGAAAGUGAUGACAACGAUGAUAUUGAUGUAGAAGCUGAAAACGAAACUGAGAAUGAAGAUGACCUAGAUCAAAAUUUUAAGAAUGAUGAUAUUGAAACAGAUAUUAACAAACUAAAACCCCAGCAAGAACCGGGACGAACAAUAGAAGAUCUAAAAAUGUAUGAACACCUUUUCCCUGAGCUUGUUGAUGAUUUUCAGGACUAUGAUUUAAUCUCCAAAGAACCAAAGCCUUUUGUAUUUGAGGGAAAAGUACGUGGUCCUAUUGUUGUUCCUACGGCAGGCGAGGAAACAUCUGGGAAUUCUGGCAAUUUAAGAAAAGUUGUAAUGAAGGAGAACAUAUCUUCUAAAGGAGAUGAAGGUGAAAAGAAGUCUACCUUUAUGGAUCUAGCAAAAGAAGAUAUUAAAGAUAAUGAUAGAACAUUACAACAGCAGCCAGGUGAUCAAAAUAGAACUAUUUCAUCAGUCCAUGGUUUAAACAAUGAUAUUGUAAAGGCCUUGGACCGAAUUACAUUGCAGAAUAUUCCUUCUCAAACAGCCCCAGGUUUUACUGCAGAAAUGAAGAAGGACUGCAGUCUUCCUCUUACUGUCCUUACCUGUGCUAAAGCAUGUCCACACAUGGCUACUUGUGGAAAUGUUCUGUUUGAGGGAAGAACAGUUCAGCUAGGGAAGCUUUGCUGCACUGGAGUUGAAACUGAAGAUGAUGAAGAUACUGAGUCAAAUUCAUCGGUAGAACAAGCAUCGGUUGAAGUACCUGAUGGACCAACACUCCAUGACCCAGACCUCUAUAUUGAGAUUGUGAAAAAUACGAAGUCUGUCCCAGAAUAUUCAGAGGUGGCUUAUCCCGAUUAUUUUGGUCACAUUCCGCCUCCAUUCAAAGAGCCUAUUUUAGAAAGGCCUUAUGGUGUACAAAGGACAAAAAUUGCUCAAGAUAUUGAAAGGCUAAUACAUCAGAGUGAUAUCAUAGAUCGUGUGGUAUAUGACUUGGAUAACCCAAAUUACACCAUUCCAGAAGAGGGAGAUAUUUUGAAAUUUAACUCCAAAUUUGAGUCUGGGAAUCUGCGCAAAGUAAUUCAAAUUAGAAAAAAUGAAUAUGAUCUUAUUCUGAACUCAGACAUAAACAGCAAUCAUUAUCAUCAGUGGUUUUACUUUGAAGUCAGUGGAAUGCGACCAGGUGUUGCUUACAGGUUUAACAUCAUUAACUGUGAAAAGUCCAACAGUCAGUUUAAUUAUGGUAUGCAACCACUCAUGUAUUCGGUUCAGGAAGCAUUAAAUGCCAGACCAUGGUGGAUUCGUAUGGGGACUGACAUUUGUUACUAUAAAAAUCAUUUCUCAAGAAGUUCAGUUGCUGCAGGUGGGCAAAAGGGAAAAUCCUACUAUACAAUUACAUUUACUGUCAAUUUUCCACAUAAAGAUGAUGUUUGCUACUUUGCUUAUCACUAUCCAUAUACGUAUUCAACUUUACAGAUGCAUCUUCAAAAAUUGGAAUCAGCACACAAUCCUCAGCAAAUCUAUUUUCGGAAAGAUGUGUUAUGUGAAACCCUGUCUGGAAACAGCUGCCCCUUGGUGACUAUAACAGCAAUGCCAGAGUCUAAUUAUUAUGAACAUAUCUGCCAUUUCAGAAAUCGCCCUUACGUUUUCUUGUCUGCUCGGGUACAUCCUGGAGAAACUAAUGCAAGUUGGGUUAUGAAAGGAACGUUGGAAUAUCUCAUGAGCAAUAACCCCACUGCUCAGAGCUUACGAGAAUCUUAUAUUUUUAAAAUUGUCCCUAUGUUAAAUCCAGAUGGUGUCAUCAAUGGAAAUCAUCGCUGUUCUUUAAGUGGAGAGGAUUUGAAUAGGCAGUGGCAAAGUCCAAGUCCGGAUUUACAUCCUACAAUUUACCAUGCUAAGGGGCUGUUGCAAUACUUGGCUGCAGUGAAGCGUUUACCCUUGGUUUAUUGUGAUUAUCAUGGCCAUUCCCGAAAGAAGAAUGUAUUUAUGUAUGGUUGCAGCAUCAAAGAGACAGUGUGGCAUACCAAUGAUAAUGCAACUUCAUGUGAUGUUGUGGAGGAUACGGGAUACAGGACAUUGCCUAAGAUACUGAGCCAUAUCGCCCCAGCAUUUUGCAUGAGCAGCUGUAGCUUCGUAGUGGAAAAAUCUAAAGAAUCCACAGCACGUGUUGUAGUUUGGAGGGAAAUAGGAGUACAAAGAAGUUAUACCAUGGAGAGUACUUUAUGUGGCUGUGAUCAGGGAAAAUACAAGGGUUUACAGAUUGGUACCCGAGAACUGGAAGAGAUGGGAGCAAAAUUUUGUGUUGGUCUUUUACGUUUGAAAAGACUGACCUCUCCAUUGGAGUAUAAUCUGCCUUCCAGCCUGCUUGACUUUGAAAAUGAUUUAAUUGAAUCAAGCUGCAAAGUAACUAGCCCUACCACUUAUGUCUUGGAUGAAGAUGAACCUCGAUUCCUUGAAGAAGUUGAUUACAGUGCAGAAAGUAAUGAUGAGUUAGAUAUUGAGUUGGCUGAAAAUGUAGGAGAUUAUGAACCUUCUGCUCAAGAAGAAGUACUUUCUGACUCUGAAUUAUCAAGAACAUACCUACCUUGAGCCCGCUGCCAUCUCUUGUUAACUGCAAAGAAUAAAUGAAAUAUCUUGGUUUUUAUUUCCCAGGAAGCUUGAGAGAAAUGAGUUUAUACAGAGCUGACUCAAAAAGACAAAAAGUAACUUGGGCCAGUUUGGUUUCAAGAUAAUAAAUGUGUUAUUAAUUAAUGAUAAAAUUGGCGCUUGUUUUAUUUUCGAUAUUCAAUGCACUUUAUGUAGCAUUGAAUGAUCAAAUAUUGGAUUUACCUUUAAAAAAAAAACCUGAGUAUCAUUGCAUGAAUUUUUAUCUCCCUAUGGUUAUAUCCUGCAUCAAGUGGAUAAUUUUGAAGUGUGUUCAGAAUAUAAAAUUGAAAUUUUAGAGUUGUUGAAAAUCCUGACUUGUUGAAAACUAAUAUAUAUGUACAUGGAUUUCUAUAGAUGUGUUUGUUUAGAAGUGGGUAGAUAUUGCAGAUAAGACUGUUCUUCAGAAUCAUGUUAACUAUUGGGUUGUGACUGAAGUAGUCCAGGGUUUGCCUUGAAACCAUUACAUUCUACAUUUACCAAAUUAAACAAAUAAAAACUGUAUUAAAUGUUGCA